GUUUCCCAAAGCCUGGAAGCAGAAGAAUAGCUGAGCCAGAGCGAACGUGAGUGUGAAACCUCUUUAAGACACCGUUGGGCUGCUUGGUUCUGACAUUCUGGACUGCAAAACAGUUCUACUAGGAUCCUGGGGAUACAUGAAGCUUCUGUGAACCAACUUUUCAAGAAAAAGCAAUGGAGAUUGGAUGGAUGCACAAUCGGAGACAAAGGCAAGUCCUUGUUUUCUUUGUUUUGCUGAGCUUGUCUGGGGCGGGCGCCGAGUUGGGGUCCUAUUCCGUAGUGGAAGAAACGGAGAGAGGCUCUUUUGUGGCAAAUCUAGGAAAAGACCUGGGGUUGGGGUUGACAGAGAUGUCCACCCGCAAGGCCAGGAUCAUUUCCCAGGGGAACAAACAGCAUUUGCAGCUCAAGGCUCAAACUGGGGAUUUGCUCAUAAAUGAGAAGCUAGAUCGAGAGGAGCUAUGCGGUCCCACUGAGCCUUGCAUACUACAUUUCCAAGUGUUAAUGGAAAACCCUUUAGAAAUAUUUCAGGCUGAACUGAGGGUGAUAGAUAUAAAUGACCAUUCUCCCAUGUUCACUGAAAAGGAAAUGAUUCUAAAAAUACCGGAAAACAGUCCUCUAGGAACUGAGUUCCCUCUGAAUCAUGCUUUGGACUUGGACGUAGGAAGCAAUAAUGUUCAAAACUAUAAAAUCAGCCCAAGCUCUCAUUUCCGGGUUCUAAUCCAUGAAUUCAGAGAUGGCAGGAAAUACCCUGAGCUAGUGUUGGAUAAAGAGCUGGAUCGGGAGGAGGAGCCUCAACUAAGAUUAACCCUGACAGCGCUGGAUGGUGGCUCUCCACCGCGAUCUGGAACUGCUCAGGUCCGUAUUGAAGUGGUGGACAUCAAUGAUAACGCUCCUGAGUUUGAGCAGCCCAUCUACAAAGUGCAGAUUCCAGAGAACAGUCCUCUUGGCUCCCUGGUUGCCACCGUCUCCGCCAGGGAUUUAGACGGCGGAGCCAAUGGAAAAAUAUCAUACACACUCUUUCAGCCUUCGGAGGAUAUUAGUAAAACUUUGGAGGUAAAUCCUAUGACAGGGGAAGUUCGACUGAGAAAGCAAGUAGAUUUCGAAAUGGUUACGUCUUAUGAAGUGCGCAUCAAAGCCACAGAUGGGGGAGGUCUUUCAGGAAAGUGCACUCUUCUCCUGCAGGUGGUGGACGUGAAUGACAAUCCCCCACAGGUGACCAUGUCUGCACUCACCAGCCCCAUCCCAGAGAACUCGCCUGAGAUAGUAGUUGCUGUUUUCAGCGUUUCAGAUCCUGACUCCGGAAACAAUGGGAAGACGAUUUCCUCCAUCCAGGAAGACCUUCCCUUUCUUCUAAAACCUUCAGUCAAGAACUUUUACACCUUGGUAACGGAGAGAGCACUCGACAGAGAAGCAAGAGCUGAAUAUAAUAUCACCCUCACCGUCACAGAUAUGGGGACUCCAAGGCUGAAAACGGAGCACAACAUAACAGUGCAGAUAUCAGAUGUCAAUGAUAACGCCCCCACUUUCACCCAAACCUCCUACACCCUGUUCGUCCGCGAGAACAACAGCCCCGCCCUGCACAUCGGCAGCGUCAGCGCCACAGACAGAGACUCGGGCACCAACGCCCAGGUCACCUACUCGCUGCUGCCGCCCCAAGACCCGCACCUGCCCCUCGCCUCCCUGGUCUCCAUCAACGCGGACAACGGCCACCUGUUCGCCCUCAGGUCGCUGGACUACGAGGCCCUGCAGGCUUUCGAGUUCCGCGUGGGCGCCACAGACCGCGGCUCCCCCGCGCUGAGCAGAGAGGCGCUGGUGCGCGUGCUGGUGCUGGACGCCAACGACAACUCGCCCUUCGUGCUGUACCCGCUGCAGAACGGCUCCGCGCCCUGCACUGAGCUGGUGCCCCGGGCGGCCGAGCCGGGCUACCUGGUGACCAAGGUGGUGGCGGUGGACGGCGACUCGGGCCAGAAUGCCUGGCUGUCGUACCAGCUGCUCAAGGCCACGGAGCCCGGGCUGUUCGGUGUGUGGGCGCACAAUGGCGAGGUGCGCACCGCCAGGCUGCUGAGCGAGCGCGACGCAGCCAAGCAGAGGCUGGUGGUGCUGGUCAAGGACAAUGGCGAGCCUCCGCGCUCGGCCACCGCCACGCUGCACGUGCUCCUGGUGGACGGCUUCUCCCAGCCCUUCCUGCCGCUCCCAGAGGCGGCCCCCGGCCAGACCCAGGCCAACUCGCUCACUGUCUACCUGGUGGUGGCGUUGGCCUCGGUGUCGUCGCUCUUCCUCUUUUCGGUGCUCCUGUUCGUGGCGGUGCGGCUGUGCAGGAGGAGCAGGGCGGCCUCGGUGGGCCGCUGCUCGAUGCCUGAGGGCCCCUUUCCAGGGCGUCUGGUGGACGUAAGCGGCACCGGGACCCUGUCCCAGAGCUACCAAUACGAGGUGUGUCUGACAGGAGGCUCAGAAACAAGUGAGUUCAAGUUCCUGAAGCCGAUUAUCCCCAACUUCUCUCCUUAGGGCACUAGGAAAGAAAUAGAUUAAAAUUCCACCCUUCACAAUAGCUUUGGAUUUAAUUAUUGAUAGGAACCCAUUUGAUAAAUUCCUUAACUUCUUAUGAUUGUCUUGUUGAUUAAAUUGUUCAUGCUCACCACCACCAAUAAGGUAUUUUUCUCUGAUUGUUAGUUCAAAUUAUAUUGUUAAUUCCAGUUUCCCUUUUCCUCAUAUUUACCCCGAAGAGGUGUUGCAUAUAGAAUCCCAAUUAACAAAAUAUACUUUAUCUUCAAAGUUGAUGUCAUUUAAAAUUUUUCCGUCUUUAUAUUUUAUUUACUUCCUAUUCAUUUUUUGCUCCAUUUUUCAUGUUACUUCUCAGUUUCCUAGAACUUCAAGUAUUAAAAUAACCUGUUGCAUGUAUUAGGCAUAUUUCCUAUGUUACAUUUCUUUUGUCUAUUUUCCUUUCAAAAUUGGUAUUUUUGUUGGGCUCAAUUUUCAUUAUAAUACUUUUCUUAAAGUUUCUUUCUUUCUUUUCUUUUCUUUCUUUUUUUUUUUUUCCUUUUUGAGACAGGGUCUUACUCUUGUCACCCAGGCUGGAGUGCAGUGGUACAAUCUUGGCUCACUGCAACCUCUGCCUCCUGGGCCCAACGGAUCCUUCCACCUCAGCCUCCCAAGUAGCUUGGACUAUAGGUGCAUGCCACCAUGCCUGGCUAAUCUUUUGCAGCGAUGGGAUUUUGCCAAGUUGCCCAGGCUGAUCUUGAACUCCUGGGCUCAAGCCAUCCUCCCUCCUCAGCCUCCCAAAAUUCUGGGAUUACAGGCAUAAGCCAAUGUGCCCAUCCAAAGUUUUAUUUAUUUAUUUUUUUGAGAUGGAGUCUCGUAAAGUUACCUUUAAAAAAAAAGUUCUAUUUUCCCUGUAUUGGUAUCUCCUUAAAUAAAAUAAAAUAUUCCUAUUGUAAGUGAUAUGAGAAAUCUUUAACCAGCCUUAUCUAAAAAUAAAAAGAGAAGCCAUUGUAAGACAUUCAGUAUGUGUAAAUGUGUUUGUGUUUGUAGACAAAAGGCAAAGGUAUUAUGUAAAAAUAUUUAAUAAUUUAUUCUUUCUAUUACUGAAUUAAAAAAUCAGAGGUCCCUGUUAUAUUUUUAAUGGCUAACAACUCAAUCUCAUUAAGUUGGAAAAAAAACUUAUCAAAGAGACAUUUACAUGGUUUGGCUUUUAUAUUCAUCAUAGUAUACAUUGGCGGUAUCUAGCCCUUUCUCUGUAAAAUAUCCCUAUGUUUAAUCUGUAUUUCUUGCUUAUUAUAUGUAAAGUUGAGCUUCUUUCUAGAUAUUAGGCCUUUGAAUAAAAUUCUAUGUGAGUCAGAUUUAA